AUGACGGACGGGCCCAGACGCCCGGUGACCCGCCAGGCGGGCUGUCCCGACCCGUCCCCACGCAGGCCCCGGCGGCAGGGGGACUUGCCAUCAGGAGAACGGGGUAGACACACUCACCUUCCAGCCGCUGGAAUCCCAGAGCUCCUGGCAGCUCCCGCCGGGUCUCUGCGGGACACUCUUCCUAAAACACACCCAGUCCGCUGCGAUUGGCUGUGGCGCGGACACUCCUGCCACCAGGAGGAGGGACAGCCCGCCCCCGCCACGGAUCUGUCCCCACCGCAGGAGCGGGACCGGCUGGGCUGCAAACACCGCCCUGAACUCCCACGGGGACCCCACAGACCAGGACUGGGGACCGGAAGACCCCUCCCAGGGGACCCCACGGUGUGUCCCAACAAGGUGUCCCCGGGGUCCCCCGGUCAGGGGCUUAGAGACAGCAAGGACGUCCCAGAGGUUCCGACCUCUCCCGCCCCGCGUGGCCCGGACCCUGGGCAGCCCGUGCCGCCUCCGUCGGUGGAAGUGGCUCCUCCCAGCGCAGCCCACGCCUGCGAUCUCCCCCCCCGAGCCAACCUGGAGCUGACCAGGAGCCCAGGUCAGGGGUCUGUCCAGGGCCCCGUUCCUGCCUCCUCCUGGCUGCUUCCGGUCCACCCCGCAGGUGCUCCCCACGCACCCCGCUGUCUCCCACCCCGGGCUGGACUCCAGGACAGGGCCAGUGUGGGCUUCAGAGAGUGCACGGAACGUUUGGGGGCCGCAGUGGACGGCUCAAAGGGCUGCCUUGGGAUCCCAUGUUCCCGGGUGGAAUUCUCCCGCAUAGCCACGGCUGGGGCUUCUCUCCCUGCACCCCAUUUCUGUCCCGGCUCCCUGUUUCCUCCCUCACCCCAGCUGUGGGGUACCUUGAGGGCGGCUGCUGUCCUGGCACAGGGACAUCUGGUCGGCCUACAAGCCACAGGCCACCGGCCUCUCCGCCUCUUUCCAUCCUAA